CUCAAAGUGCUGGGAUUGCAGGCUUGAGCCAUAAUGCCCUGCCUGACUCUCUUUCUACCAAACAUUUAUGUUUCAUCUCUGAUGCUGUUAGAGAGAUUUCAUUUGAUUUGAACUAUGGGAUCAGAAGAAUUCCAUUAGGGAGGAGUGUCUGGAAUCUUUUUCUUUUGAAGACACAACUGUCUUCUCCUUAGAUUAUCUGGGAGAUAGAGUAGUCAAAGCUGUUGUGGUUUUUUCAGAGAGGAUCCUGAAAUUUGUUUUACCUAUCUCUGUUUCUUUGUAUUGAGAAAUGGUUUAUUAGGAUAUUAAGUAAUUAAACAUAUAUUGAAGAAAUAAAGAUGAUUUUCUUUUUGAUAUCUCAGAUUCCUAUUCAUAUGACUGAUUCUUGUAAGGAAGGACUGGGACCUUAAGAUUUUGCUGAGUGAGGGAGGUGGCCUGUUUUUUUAAGGUAUAUGAAUGACCUAAAGGUACAAAUAAAGACGGAGAGAGAACAGUGCCAACUGGGAGCAGGGCAAGAAUGCCAAUUCCUCCUCCCCCGCCACCCCCACCUGGUCCUCCUCCACCUCCCACAUUUCAUCAGGCAAACACAGAGCAGCCCAAGCUGAGUAGAGAUGAGCAGCGGGGUCGAGGCGCCCUCUUACAGGACAUUUGCAAAGGGACCAAGCUGAAGAAGGUGACCAACAUUAAUGAUCGGAGUGCUCCCAUCCUCGAGAAGCCGAAAGGAAGCAGUGGUGGCUAUGGCUCUGGAGGAGCUGCCCUGCAGCCCAAGGGAGGUCUCUUCCAAGGAGGAGUGCUGAAGCUUCGACCUGUGGGAGCCAAGGAUGGUUCAGAGAACCUAGCUGGUAAGCCAGCCCUGCAAAUCCCCAGUUCUCGAGCUGCUGCCCCAAGGCCUCCAGUAUCUGCCGCCAGCGGGCGUCCUCAGGAUGAUACAGACAGCAGCCGGGCCUCACUCCCAGAACUGCCCCGGAUGCAGAGACCCUCUUUACCGGACCUCUCUCGGCCUAAUACCACCAGCAGUACGGGCAUGAAGCACAGCUCCUCUGCCCCUCCCCCACCACCCCCAGGGCGGCGUGCCAACGCACCCCCCACACCUCUGCCUAUGCACAGCAGCAAAGCCCCCGCCUACAACAGAGAGAAACCCUUGCCACCGACGCCUGGACAAAGGCUUCACCCUGGUCGAGAGGGACCUCCUGCUCCACCCCCAGUCAAACCACCUCCUUCCCCUGUGAAUAUCAGAACAGGACCAAGUGGCCAGUCUCUGGCUCCUCCUCCUCCGCCUUACCGCCAGCCUCCUGGGGUCCCCAAUGGACCCUCUAGCCCCACUAAUGAGUCAGCCCCUGAGCUGCCACAGAGACACAAUUCUUUGCAUAGGAAGACACCAGGGCCUGUCAGAGGCCUAGCACCUCCUCCACCCACCUCGGCCUCCCCAUCUUUACUGAGUAAUAGGCCACCUCCCCCAGCCCGAGACCCUCCCAGUCGGGGAGCAGCUCCUCCACCCCCACCACCUGUGAUCCGAAAUGGUGCCAGGGAUGCUCCCCCUCCCCCACCACCAUACCGAAUGCAUGGGUCAGAACCCCCGAGCCGAGGAAAGCCCCCACCUCCACCCUCAAGGACGCCAGCUGGGCCACCCCCUCCUCCUCCACCGCCCCUGAGGAAUGGCCACAGAGAUUCUAUCACCACUGUCCGGUCUUUCUUGGAUGAUUUUGAGUCAAAGUAUUCCUUCCAUCCAGUAGAAGACUUUCCUGCUCCAGAAGAAUAUAAACACUUUCAGAGGAUAUAUCCCAGCAAAACAAACCGAGCUGCCCGUGGAGCCCCACCUCUGCCACCCAUUCUCAGGUGAAGCCUGGCUUGGUCCCGUUCCUCAGGAAAAGGAUGGACCUUCUCUUCUUCUCAGAUGGUCCCUUCCAUUCCCCUGAAACCUGCAUGAGAGCUCCUAACAUGUUUCUCCAAUGCAAUCAAGCCCUAGACUCCAAAUGUCCUCCCAGCUCACCUCCAUCUAUGCAUCUCAUCUCUGGAUUUGGUGAUCAGACUCUAUAUUGACAGUAGGAUCUCAAACCCUGCAUCCAUCCUUCCUCCAGCAAGCCCUGCUAGCCACAUGAGGAACAAGUUUCCGUGUCUUCUGCCUUCCUCUUGGGGAAAGGUGCCUUGUUGUGAUGAAUUAACUCACUGUUAGGGCAGGGUGGAGAAUGGUACUCCUUCCUUCUCCUGUCCACUGUGGGGGAAGCUUGGCAGGUAUAUUAUAUUUCAUCAUUUAGGAGGCUGGCAUGACCAGGACUUAUGGGUGGGAGGGGAGCAUUUUUAGUGAAGCAAGAAAGGAGUUUGCCAAGAAGUGAUCUGUUUUAAAGGUCAUAUUUGGAGAAAGGGCAAGGAAUUGGGUCUGCUUUAUUUUUGGGGGUAUUUUGUUUUUGUUCUCACCUGCUGCCCCCCCACCCCACCACCCCAGGGAUAAAUUGGAUAUAAACACUAAAUACUAAUCAGUUGAACUUAACAUUUAAUAAAAAGAAAGGGUGAAAUAAACUGAAGACCAUUUUAGAACUAGUCAGUUCUCUGCAGCAAAGGGAACAGGAGCCAUUUGAACCCUCUGGGACCCCUCACCCCACUGCUUCAGGGUGCUAGGCUGAGGGAUGUUUUUCCUCCCCCUUACCGCCCAUGCCCUUGAAAGAAAAGUCACUUUUUGUGGAGGGCAUCAUUCAUUCCUGAUUCACAAACCCCAAAAACCUCUGGUGGGAGAUAGGAAGAUAGGGCGUGGGCCUGGGCCUUAACCUCAAUCUUGUGUCUGCCUCAGUCUUUUCUGACUGGCCCUGAAGUUGUCAGUGGCUCUUUCUGUCCUUCAGCCCCUGGAAGGUGCUCCAGGAUAACAAAGAAGGGCAGGUUGAAGCCCCUCAUGGAAGGAGCUGGCUUUGUGGGGCUGCAAAGGACUUUUAAGUCCUGCCUGUACUGAAGUUCACAGCCCACCUGACUGAGCAGACUCUUCCUGUUCCUUUCUCUACCACCCUUGCCUUCCCAGGACUGCACGGUUUAACACAGCAGAGUACAGAAGGGUGAAGAAGUGAGCAGAGGCUUAUGAAGAUAUUCAGAUACUCUUCUAUGCCAGGAAGCACAAAGACUUUGUUGAGAUUUGCCUCAGUUCAGUAGAUCUUCCUUGGCAGCCAGCCAUAGGUUGUUUCUUUGUCUUCCGGGUCCUAAAGAGCACAGAGAAAAUGGAGGUCCCCAGUCUAGGUAGGAAGCUGAUUGGAUGAGGACUUCUUUUUUUCCGACAGCAGGAUGGGGCUCUUGGGCUCCACACACCAGAUGCUUUGGUUUUCUACAACUGUUGCUAUGUGUAGAGGGUGCUCAGAGCGUGGCAUGAGAGCAAGGAGACCAUGGCUACUCUUUGAAAUGGAUGGGGAAAAUUAGCUUAAAAAUUUAAUCACGAGAUUGCGCCACUGCACUCCAGCCUGGGCGACAGAGCCAGACUCCGUCUCAAAAAAAAAAAAAAAAAAAAAAUUUAAUCACACACAUCACAGGCUUAAACUGUCUUAGAGACCUUUCCAGUUGAUUGGAUCACAGGCUAGGGAUCUGUGCAUGGUGCCAGGUGAAACCCAAGUCUCCCCAGUGCUAGGUGAGGGAGGGCUCAACGGGGGUAAUGUGUAUGGGGUCUGCUGUCCUUUGCCAUCCCCUGGACCAUAUUAACUCUGGGACAGACCAUGAUUAGGUCUGUCACCAAACUUUUCCUAAUCAUUUUUUAUGUAUCAUUCUUCUUUCUAAUCUGUUAGCAGUUAUCUCCCAGAAGUAUCCCUAGCAUCCUGAAGCAAACAGAACUGCCGGGCGCUGUGGCUUAUGCCUGUAAUCUCAGCAAUUUGGGAGGCCGAGGCGGGCGGAUCACCUGAGGUCAGAAGUUCGAGACCAGCCUGUCCAACAUGGUGAAACCCCGUCUCCACUAAAAACACAAAAAUUAUCUGGGCGUGGUGGCAUGUGCCUGUAGUCCCAGCUACUGGGGAGGCUGAGGCAGGAGAAUCGCUUGAAUCCAGGAGGUGGAGGUUGCAGUGAGUGGAGAUGGCGCCACUGCGCUCCAGCCCGGGUGACAGAGUGAAACUCCAUCUCAGAAAACAAACAAACCAAACAACUGAGAGAGGGCAUGCUAGUGGAGGGAAAAGGAGAGAGUACAAGAGUUGAUACUGCAUCAGAGUUCCAGGGCAGAUACUGACAAGUGACUGAACUUUGACUGUGAAGUCUUCCCAUUUAUUUUUGAAAUGGGAGUCGAUGCCUUUUGUACGUUAUCAAAGUGUUUUUUUUUUUUUCCUCCUUUACUCAGACAUAGAGCAUCAAAAUAUCACGAGUAAAGCCAAACCCCAGCUUUUCACUGGGGCUGAUAUCUUCCUCCCCAUGGCCCACUGCCCCCUCAUAUUCCCCAGCACUUGGACUGUGUCACAUGGGUAUUGAUUGUAUACUUGUUGUCUUGGCCUCAUGCAAAAAGGCCUGGGUCUAGAUCUAGUCAGAUGAGUUUUUUUUAGAGCAUGUUGAUGAUACAACACCUGUUUAAAUGUCUGCCUUAUAUGUUAUUUGGUCCCACUGUUAAUAAUAGAUUUAUUACUAUGUAUAUUUACUAUUGAAGAUGGGAAUGUGAUCUGCAUAGUUAUCAGUCUAUUUUGUAUGUUGUAAAAAGCUUCUAAUUUAGGUUUAAGGUGGGCUGGCUACAAGAGCACUAAAACUCCUCACCUUUUAAACUGCUCUUUUUAUCUGCUUGUGGGAAUGUCGUCUCUUUCGUGGAAGAUUGGGUGGUCUCAUGUUGAGGCUGUUGCCCAGUCCCAUUAACUCCCUUGUCCCCCCACAGAAGGAAGAGACAUUGCCCAGCUAAGCAUCAGGAAGCUGUGUUAAAAGCCCUUCUAUGGGUUUGGUUUUGUGAUGUUUUUCCCUAAUGGGAAAAACGUUAUAGUUGUUUCUUACUGCCCUGUCUGGGAAGCAGGGCAAACCUCCAGGUUUUUAAAUGAGCUAGAUGCCCCUCUUCCUCUUCUCUGGUCACUGAACCUGGACCAAAGCACUUUGAUAUUCCAGGUGUGAUUUUCUCUGUCAUGGGGAUUUGCUCCACUGCAGAGCCCCAUCAUUUUCACAGCGUAGGCCAACAGAGUGAGAACCUAGGGCUACCCUAGCUGAUGGAUGUGAGGCUGCUGUCUACAGGAGCUCAUCCCAGCCCUGUUAACUGGCAGUGGCAAGGAUACUCGUCAUCGGCCAUUGCACUGGGGAACUCCCUCACCCCAUGGCUUCCCAACUUGAAACCCAGAUUUACCUCCAGGGAGAGGUGAGAAAAAAAUUGUAAAUAGACUUGCUAAAGAGCAACUCAGGGUUGGGGUGUGUUUUAAUUCUCCUGAUCACUUGAAAUAAUCUGUAGGCUGAGUGCUUAUGGGGGUGGGGGAGAAGGGUGACUCCAGGGUCCUUCCAUUUUGUGAAGCUCUGGGGGUGGAGUGUGGGCAUCUGAGGCCCUAUGAUGGCACUACAUUGAGCUGUCUGCCCUUCCGGAAACCCAACCUGCAAUCAACUGCAAAUCAAAUUCUUCACAUUCCAGCUACAGUCUUUCUUUCCCCAUUGAAUCUCAGUCCCUGGCCAUGUGGUCAAGGUGGCUUUCUGUUAAGCUACCCUAAUUUCGGGAAUGGGAGGGGAGAGAGGAGGGCCAUUACAACUCUGCCUUCAAGACUCAUCUCUUAAAAACAAAACGAAACAAAACUACAACCACCAUCAAAACCACACGCAAAAAAAAAAAAAAAAAAAAAAAGGAUAACUUUAACCGAAGGAAGGGUUUGGUUCCAUUCAACUCCACAUUCAUUGUGCCUUUACUUGCAUUAGAUUUCUGUGCUUUCUUCCUUUCCCUCUUUGAAGCAAUUAAAAUCUUCCUUGAUAACUGCUGUUUCUUUCUACUCUUGUUUCUGGCAAUUUAGUGGGUUCCUUCUCUAGUGGUCUUAAAUCUCAUUCCACUGGUGGCAAGAUGGGGCCUAGCCUUCUUUUCACAUGUCUAAUCUUUUCCUUUCUCAUGGUGCCCUCCAUGGAAGUCACAGUCAACACUGAAUAAAUGACUAGAAUGACACGUGUGCGUGCGCACGCGUGUGCGUGUGUGUGUUCAUCUGUCUGCAUGUGGAUCAAUUUCUUUUAGAAAAUAAUUUAUUGUAUGAUUUAUUUUGGAGUUAUAUUCUGAUUACAGUGCUCCCUCUCCCAAAUAGCAUUGAUUUUUUCCCCCCUCUAAAAUGUAUAAUCUGGUCUCAGGUUGGAUUCUUUGGUACAUUUCUCUCUUCUGGAUGCCAUGCAGCUUAAUUAAAACCUUGCUUAAAAACAAAAAGUGAAAAUUGUGUACUCUUGUCUGGAAUACCGCCUCAGGUGGUGGCACAGAGAGGGGAGAAAACCUUUGCCUCAUAAUUUGGGUAAGUGUAGUGGUUUGAUUCCAGGUCCCUUGAAAAAGUAGAUCUACUGAAUUGGGCAGACUCAUCUAUAGCUUUCUGAGGGUCUUCUCUCCUCCUCUCCAGCUGUAUUUUGAAAAUUACAGUUCUAGUUGGCUGGGCGCGAUGGCUCAUGUCUGUAAUCCCAGCACUUUGGGAGGCCAAGGCGGGUGGAUCAUUUGAGGUCAGGAGUUCAAGACCAGCUUGGCCAACAUGGUGAAACCCCGUCUCUACUGAAAAUACAAAAAUUAACCGGUGUCAUGGCGCAUGCCUGUAGUCCCAGCUACUCGGGAGGCCGAGGCAGGAAAAUCACUUGAACCCAGGAGGCGGAGGUUGCACUGAGCUGAGAUCAUGCCACUGCACUAAAAAAAAAAAAAAAAAAAAAAAAAAAAAAAAAAAAAAAUUCUAGAGUUCUAGUUACCCUUCCUGGGAGAUUCUGAUGGUCCUUAUUUUAUUAUUAUUAUUAUUUUUUUUUGAGACAGGAUGUUGCUGUCAUCCAGGCUGGAGUGCAGUGGUGUGAUCAUAGCUCACCGCAGCCUCCAACUCUCAAGCUCAAGUGAUCCUCCCACCUCAGCCUCCCGUGUAGCUGGGACCACAGGUGUGUACCACUAUGCCUGGCUAAUUUUGAAAAUUUUUUUGUAAAGACAGGGUCUCCCUAUGUUGCCCAGACUGGUCUCAAAUUCCUGGGCUUAAGUGAUUGUCCCACCUCAGCUUCUCAAAGUGCUGGGAUUACAGGCAUGAGCCACCGCACCCAGCCAGUCCUUAUUUUAUAUUUCCACCUAACUCCCCUUUGCCCACGAUUUCAGGGAACCUAGGAGGCUUCCUGGCCUUGUGACCUUUUCCUUGAAUCUCUUAUAAUUCUUUCUACCUGUGUUGCAUGGCAGAUUCUCAGAUUGAGGCUAAAGAAAAGAAGGGUGGGGACAAAGCAUACAGAAUGUGUGUAUCUGUUUUUAUGUGGGUGUUGGCUGUUUUUCGUCACUGCUUUUUAAGCUGAAUCUUAGCUGGUUUUCUUGAACUUUGACUUUAGGUGUAAAAAUUCAACCAGACAUUCUCUCCUUACUGUGGUCAGCUGACAUCAUAACCACUAAGGCUUAAUGAGCUUAACUUGCACUUUCAUCACUAGCAAAGGUCUUGAAGUUAUUUCUCUUACUGAUUCAUAAUGGGUGUGUGUAUGAAUCACUCUCACAUAAUUUAGAUAUAAAAACCUAUGAGGAUGAGGGAGGGAGGGGAAGAAAAAAAAGGACUCCUUUCAUUUUCAUCCGUACUUCCCAGAUGGGCUGAAUCUCCGAUUAUUUGACCCAUCAUUGUUAUUAAUAUGGUUAAUAAACUACCUAUUUAUUGAUUGAA